GGCCUCCCUCGUCCCGCGGCCGGGUCCCCGCGCGUCCCCGCCGCCCGGGAGUCCGCCCGCGGCCUGCGUGGCGUCCCUCCCCGGCGUGUGUCGCCCCUUUUUGGGUCUGGUCAGCUCCUCUUCCCUCCUCCCGCCCAUACUCAAAGCGGGCAAAAAUCACCACGAAAGUUUGUGGAAUGAAUGAAUGAAUGAACUUGAAGGGCCCUUCCGCAUUUAAUGUGCAGGGACUGAUGUUGCGAAUGGACGGCGCCCGGGCGUUACAAGGAGUGUGCCGUGAGUCACACGUUGCCUUCCAUCUCGGACUUAGUUGUCUGAACUGUGAGGGAUUGCAGGGAGCGCUUUCCAGUGAAAUACUUCUUUGAUGUCUACUUCUGUGUUUGGUAAUUCUGCUGGGAAUCUAAGGAUGAAAAGACAAUGCCUGACCAUCAAGGAACUUACAGUCUGUUGGUCAAAGACAUGCAAAUAACUGAUCACUGUACAAGAUAAUUGAAGGUAUGUACAGAGUGCAGUGGCAACAUUGAAGCACUGCCAGAGACUGGAGAAAUCCAGGAAGAUUUCAGGAGCAGAGACUUGAAGGAUGAGAAGGUUUGCUGGGCAGGCAUAUAGAAGGACGCCAUGGCAUGUGCAGAAGCACAGAGGCGUAGGAGACCGUGGUGUUCGGGAAAAUAAGUACUGUAAUUUAAUGAUACUGAGCGGAAAAGCCUGGUUGAUUGUAGCCUCUGGUCUUCAAGCGCCUUGAAUGCCAAGCAAAUGACUUUAUAACUAGAUAAAAGAGAGCCACUGGAGAAAUUUGAGCUGAGGCAAGAAUCUGCCUCUCCCUUAACUACCUCAGUGGCUUGUUUUCUACAUUUGAUUCAGAACACCACUCCUGAAGUUGUCUUUGGGCAUUGCUUUGAUAACGUGUCUACCAGUUAGACCCUAAAUACUCAGACAACUGGUUUCAUAUGCAUGAUAUGCAUUUAGGUAAAAUAAUUCCGACUCUAUUGACAGAAACGCAUGUGUGUAUAUCAGGGUUUCACAAACUUUUUCUUUAAAGGGCCAGAUAGUAAAUAAUUUAGGCUUUGUAGGUGAUAUCAUCUCUCACAUUUAUUCAGCUGUGCUUUGUAGCCAUGGACAUAUAACAAACCCGUUUAUGUUACAAUAAAACUUUUUAUGGCCACUGAAAUUUCAAUUUCAUAUAGUUUUCCAUAAGUCACAGAAUAUUAUUAUUUUGAUUUUUCUCCAACCCCCCUCCUCCUUUUUUUUUUUUAAGAGACAAGGUCUUUGUCACCCAGGAUGCAGUGCAGUGGUACAGUCAUAGCUACUGCAGCCUCAAAUUCCUGGCCUCAAGGGAUCCUCUUGCCUCAGUCUCCCCAAAUGCUGGGAUUACAGGCAUAAUCCACCAUGCCCAUCCCCAUUUUAAAAAUAUAAGAAUCAUUGUUAGCUUACAGGAUUUACAAAAACAGGCACUGAGCUGGAUUAGCUAGUUUGUCAAUCUCUAAUGUAUGUUAAAGACUCUCAGUUAAAAUCCAAAUGAUACAUGACUUAAAGUUGUGUAUAUGUUUUAUAUGUACAUAUAUUAUAUAUACAUAAAUAUAUUUAAACAAACGAAAAAGUUUACAGACAGUUUCUAUUAAAUAUCUUAACAGAAGGAAAGUUACAUUUAUGAUUCUGCAUGGUUUACCCCUGUGAUCUGUGACUUUUCUUUUUUUACCUUUUUUAGUCUUAGAAAGACUUCUCAGCCUGGGCAACAUAGCAAGAUUCCAUCUCUACUUAAAAUAAAAAUUUUAAAAAUUACCUACUUGGGAGGCUGAGGCAGAAGGAUCAGUUGAGCCCAGGAGCUCAAGGUUGCAGUGCAUUAUGAUUGUGCCACUGCACUCCAGCCCGGGCAACAUAGCAAGACCCUUUCUCUAAAUAAAUAAAUAAAAUGGAACUUUUUGGACAACCUUACUUUCAUUCCUUUGGAUUCCCUUUGUUUCCUUUCAGGCCUCUUGAUUUCUGGCUUCCAGUUAAAAAGGUGCCGUAUAGUUCUGAAAACUCACCCAACUAGUUUCUUACAUUUCUGCCACCAACAUUCACUUCCAAGUCCUGAAGUCUUUCCCUCUUCAAGAACCAACUGAAUAGCUGGUUAUUCAUGCCUUGUAAUCUCAGCACUUUGGGAGGCCAAGGCUGGUAGACUGCCUGAACUCAGAAGUUUGAGACCAGUCUGGGCAACAUGGCAAAACCCAUCUACCAAAAAAAUCCAAAAUAUCAGCCAGGCGUGGUAGUGCACAGCUGUGGUCCCAGCUACUGGGGAGGCUGAGGUGGGAGGAUCUCUUGAGCCUGGGAGGCUGCAGUUGCAUUGAGCUGAGAUUGUGCCACUGCACACACACAAAAGAACUAAUUGGAAAAGAGGAAAAAUCUUCUCAAGCUGUAGCCUGUUGUACACAACUUAGAAAGUUUCCCUUAUUAUCACUCCCAUUCGACAGUGUAGAAUUUCCCUGAAUGCCACUAUUAUGCUACAUAUAUCCAAGUACCCAGAUAACAAAAAUAUUGUGAACUUCAGUGAUCUAAAGCAGGACAUCUCAAACUGGGGUUCACAAACAGAAAUUAUAGGGUCUUUGUCCUUGGGUGGGGGGAAGAACUGUAUCUUUAUUUUCAGUAAACUCCUGCUUAAAUUGAACAUUUCCUUCAAUUAUGAAUGUAGGCAGUACCUGUUGAUACUAUUAUAUUCCCAGUCUCUAGCACAAUGCUUGCUAGAGAUGCUGAGUAACUAUUGUAGAUGAAAAGAAAUAAGGGGUGGAGGGAGGGAUGAUUGAAAUAUGUCAAGAUGGAAGGAUAUAAAUACUUAUUUUCUACUCAGUCUUCUACCUUCAUCAGUAAUAAUAUCUUCAUAAAAUAAUCUUACCUCCUGGCUGUGUAGUACUUUAGUGUUUUAUACUAUGGCUUGCUUAAUUUGUCCUCCAAAAUAGUCUUGUAAGGUAGGAAGGAUAGAUAUUACUGUCUUUACACAUAAGAAACUGGGCUCAGUGAAGCUAAAAUGCCUUGCCCAGUGGGCUCCACAGUGAAUGUGUCAGAGCCAAGGCAGGAACAGCCCUUUGAACUUCUACUUCAUUGCUCUUUCUGUUUUAUCAAAUCAUCCUUAAUAUGAUUGUCGUACGUCAGUUUACAAUAAGAUCUUGGAGGGUGUUCGUCGUUGGCAGCUAGCCAGAUAUUUUUGGAGGAUUUCCAUUUAGCCUCAUGGUACAACACCUUAGCCUUCUGGGAUUUUGUUUCCCUUGACCGUGUGGGGUCAACACUUUUGCUGCAGCUGUAGAGGGCCUUAAUGAGCUUCCUAAACAACAGAGGAGGAGAUGACUCCAUUGUAUCCGAAGUGCCAGAAGUAUUCCUCCAACUGUGACUGCUGCAAAGCUACAUUCAAAUAUUGGCUCUGCUGCUCAUUAUGUAUGUGACCUUGGGCAAGUUACUUUAUUUCUUGGAGCAUUGGUUUCUUGAUCUAUAAAAUGGGAGUGACAGAUACCUACCUCAAAUUUCUUGUAGGAAAUAAAUGACAUAGAAAAUACAUAUGAAAGUCUCAAGCCCAUAAAAAGUGCUAAGUGAAUUUCUAAAUAUGCUUUUGAUUUCUUACCAAAUCAAACGUGUUCAAGAUUUCUGAUUCUAAUGAUGUAACACUUUGAUGCUGCCAACCUCCUUUUGUCUACAUAGUCACUGCAUUCUCAUCCAGUUAGCUAUUUUUCUUAAGUUUGAAUUUAUUGAGUAGAAAACUCAAGCUGAGCCUCAAUUCUUUUUUUUUUUUUUUUUUUUUGAGACAGAGUCUAGCUUUGUUGCCCAGGCUUGAGUGCAGUGGCGCGAUCUCGGCUCACUGCAACCUCCGCCUCCUGGGUUCAAGUGAGUCUCCUGCCUCAGCCUCCUGAGUAGCUGGGAUUACAGGUGCGCAUCAUCAUGCCCGGCUAAUUUUUGUAUUUUUAGUAGAGAAGGGGUUUCACCAUGUUGGUCAGGCUGGUCUCAAAAUCCUGACCUUGUGAUCCACCUGCCUUGGCCUACCAAAGUGCUCGGAUUACAGGCGUGAGCCACCACGCCUGCCGUUGAGCCUCAAUUCUAUCCCACUAUAUUAGUACCCAGAGCUAAUGAGAAUUUUCAUGCCUUCCAUUUGAAGGAAUUUGAAAUUUCACUCUUCUCAUUUUCUCUUUUAUGAGGUUAGAAUUCUUAUUUCUGUUUCAGUCCUGAUCCAUAUUAUCUUGCAUUGAUUCUAACAUUAAUUUCAUGUCAACAAUGACACAGGCAUGACAGAUUACUGUAAAAAAUAACUGAACAUUUAAAAUAUAUAUUUCCAAUGGCUAUAUUAUAGUUGUAUACAUACAUUUUGAAAUGUAACUUUUAAAUGAUAUUUCAGCGACAAAAAAUAUUACAACUGGAAGCGACCAUAAUUCUUUAGUCUGAUACUUUCAAUUUACAAAUAAUUGACGCAUUUUGAAGCUAGUUGUUUUUUUCUGUCUUUCCCAAAAGUCACAUAGUCAAUAAUAUUCUUGUCUUAUAACUGUUUUGUUUAUUUAAAAUAAUAAUAUAUGGAGAAUAAGACUGUUUGAUCAGGAAAUAAGAAAACCUUUUUGUACAUUUCCAGUUUGGGGAGGGAGCAAUGAAAAUGGCUUUCCAAUUCCCAGACUUUCCUCUUCAGAUUUCGAUCUGCUGUGCCAUGUUGCCUUUCUGAAACCAUGUGGGAAAUAAUGCAAAGCAAUAAUUUAUGUGUUUCAUUUGUGCAGUUCAGGUAACUGGCCAACAUUUCUAAUAAUUUCCUAUUAAAUUAUUACCACUUUAUAGCAUCUUCCAUGUUUAUUAUACUUCAUUUAGGUUAGCAGAUUUAUUUCGUAAUUUUAUCAUACUUGUUUCAAGGAUCCUAAAAUGUAUAUGUUUGGUACUCGAUUAUUAAUAUUUAAUAGCAAGAUGUCAGAUACCACAUUGUUAUUACUAAAUUGAAGAGACUGAGAAACAUUUCUGCAGACUCACAAGAAAAAAAACCCUUAAAGAUCAAAAGAAAGUAGAUAUUACACUCACUCGAUUUAGAAACUAAGAAUUUCACAAACGUGUUUAGUAAUUUCAAAAGAUAUAUUUUAAAUAUUCUAAAUUUUAUAAUAUGCGAAGUGAAAAACAACUUUGGUCACAAUUUUCCUUUUGCUAGGACUGUGGAUUUCCAAGGAUUCAUUACUUUUUUAGCAUUUUCCUUUGAUAUGGUGAUCUAAAUGGUAUAUCCUCUGCACUCUCUGAAGGAAGAAGUUUCAAAGUUUAUUCCUGGCCACAGUAACACUAAUCACAACAGUAUCAUUUCAAAGCCUAAAUGUCAGCUAAUAGGAAAGGGAAAGUUUGUUGAAUAGUUAUUAUUUACGUAGAACAGAAACCCCACAAAACUUUGAAGGUGGAAUGGAUUAUUACAGUGUAACUGUUUCAUUUCAAGCUGAGGAAACAGACUCAGAAGUAAUCUCUAGUAUUUACAAAGAUGUGUAUGUGUGUGUUUGUGUGUGUGUGUGUGUGUGUGAGCUUGUACAAGAGUCUGGUAACUAGCUGUAAUCUCUCUCUACGUAAGGAAAUGGCCUUAGAAGUACCACUUGAAAUUUGGGCUUAAUAAACGGGGAAAUUUUCACAGAAAUGAAGGUUAUUAGAUACUGAAAUGGUAUACAAAGAAAGCUUGUGUGUGUUUUAUAAGGAGGAAGUUCGAUUACUAGAGAGAUCUGUCAUGCUUAGAGUCCAUGGAUUUUUAACUAUUUGGGCUUUAAUCCUACCCAAAGGAGGAAAGACCAAAUAAGCAAAAAGUUUAUUUUUUAUUUGCUUUUAAAAAAUGAUUUGCUUUUGUUCAUGCAGUAAAUCUUUAUUGAAUGACUAAUGAUUCAAAUGUUGAGUCUGAUCCGUGGUUUGAAUACAUGAACCAGACCAAGCUCUGUGGCUCAAGCCUGUAAUCCCAACACUUUGGGAGGCUGAGGCAGUGGGGAUCGCUUGAAGUCAGGAGUUUGAGAUCAGCCUGGGCAACACAGCAAGACCCCCUCCAACCCAUCCCGCCCCCCACCAUCUCUACAAAAAAUUUCAAAAAUUAGCUGGGCAUGGUGGCACACUCCUAUAGUCCCAGCUACUCAUGGGGCUGAUGCAGGUUGAGGCAGGAGGUUCAUGAGCCCAGGAGGUUGGAGCUGUAAUGAGCUAGGAUUCUGCCUCUGCACUCCUAGCUGGAUGACAGAGCAAGACCCUGUCUCAAAAAAGAAAAAAAAAAAAAAAAGAAUGCAUGAACCAGACAUGACAGUUCCUGGCCUCAAAGAUCUUCCAAAGGAAAUGAUUUUUUUUUAACCACCAAUGCUGCAGGAAAAAGCAACAUAUUUAAGUUAUCCAAUAACACCUAUCCAAUAAUUGUAAAUCAUUAUCAUGACAUGGUAGAGUUGUUUAUAUUUCUUUUCCUUUUAGGUGAAACACCAUUCAAAGUCGUAGUCAAAUCUCUUUCACCUAAAGAGUUGGUCCGGAUACAUGUCCCUAAACCUUUGGACAGGAAUGAUGGAACAUUUUUGAUGAGAUAUAGGAUGUAUGAAACUGUCGAUGAAGGCCUGAAGAUAGAGGUCCUUUAUGGUGAUGAACAUGUGGCUCAGUCUCCCUAUAUUUUGAAAGGACCAGUGUACCAUGAGUACUGUGAGUGUCCGGAAGAUCCUCAGGCCUGGCAGAAGACUCUUUCUUGUCCAACCAAGGAACCACAGAUUGCAAAAGAUUUUGCUUCCUUUCCCAGCAUCAAUCUCCAGCAAAUGCUAAAAGAAGUCCCCAAAAGGUUUGGGGAUGAGAGAGGUGCCAUUGUUCAUUACACGAUUCUCAAUAACCAUGUUUACCGGAGAUCUUUAGGGAAAUACACAGACUUCAAGAUGUUCUCUGAUGAGAUUUUGUUAUCAUUGACAAGAAAGGUCCUUCUCCCAGAUUUAGAAUUUUAUGUUAAUCUUGGAGAUUGGCCCUUGGAGCAUCGAAAAGUCAAUGGAACCCCUAGCCCCAUACCUAUCAUUUCAUGGUGUGGCUCUCUGGAUUCAAGAGAUGUUGUCCUUCCAACGUAUGACAUCACCCACUCCAUGCUUGAAGCCAUGCGGGGUGUUACAAAUGAUCUCCUCUCUAUUCAGGGAAAUACAGGGCCUUCCUGGAUCAAUAAAACAGAGAGAGCUUUCUUCAGAGGUAGAGACAGCCGAGAGGAGAGGCUCCAGUUGGUACAGCUGUCCAAAGAAAAUCCUCAGCUACUAGAUGCAGGAAUUACAGGAUAUUUCUUUUUCCAAGAGAAAGAAAAGGAGCUUGGAAAAGCCAAGUUGAUGGGUUUCUUUGAUUUCUUUAAGUACAAGUAUCAAGUAAAUGUGGAUGGGACCGUGGCUGCUUACAGAUAUCCAUAUCUCAUGCUGGGCGACAGUCUGGUUUUAAAGCAGGACUCGCCAUAUUAUGAACAUUUCUACAUGGCACUAGAACCUUGGAAGCAUUAUGUUCCAAUUAAAAGAAAUCUGAGUGAUUUAUUAGAGAAAGUUAAAUGGGCUAAGGAAAAUGAUGAAGAAGCCAAGAAGAUUGCAAAAGAAGGACAGUUGAUGGCUAGGGACCUACUACAGCCACACAGGCUUUACUGCUACUAUUACCAAGUACUGCAGAAAUAUGCCGAGCGCCAGUCCAGCAAACCCGAAGUACGUGAUGGAAUGGAACUUGUUCCUCAGCCAGAAGAUAGCACAGCCAUCUGCCAGUGCCACAGGAAAAAGCCUUCAAGAGAAGAACUUUGAGUCAGCCCAGAAUCACACUCCUGUGUAUCCCGGCUACACUUUAAGGAAAGAUUGAAUCUAAGCUGUGAAGGACAGUAUAGAAGACUGCACCAAGUGGACUAGUUCUCCCGGUGGCUUUAUAUAUGUAGAUGGAUAUAGCAGUACUGGUUGAGUAUCCCUCAUCUGAAAUGCUUAGGACCAGGAGUGUUUCAGGCUUCAGAUUUUUUAAGAUUUGGGAAUAUUUGCAUGUACAUAAUGAGGUAUCUUGGGGAUGAGAUCCAAGUCUAAACACAAAAUUCAUUUAUAUUUUAUAUAUACCUUGUUCACAUACCCUGAAGGUAAUUUUAUAUAAUAUUUUUAAUAAUUUGUGCAUGAAACAAAGUUUGUAUACAUUGAACUGUCAGAAAGCAAAGGUGUCACUAUCUUAGCGACCCAAGUGGUGGUGUCAGCACUCAAAAAGUUUUGGAUUUUGGGGUAUUUCAGAUUUUAGAUUUUUGUAUGAGGAAUGUUCAACCUGUAUUUGAACAAGCAUUACCAAAUAUCAUUGAAUAUUAAUAUCUUUUGCGUAAAAACUGCUAUUAUCAGCAUCAUAGUUUCUCUAAAAAGAAAACUUGGGGAUCAUAGCCGAUAGAGAGACUUGCUAAAAUAUAAAUCAGCCUCUGCAAAACUGUUUACAUAUUUAUUGGUUUACAUAUUUUAUUGGUUUAUUUCUAUCCCCUGUUCACUUUUUCUCUUCCACUUCCAAUUAUGAAGAGAAAAUAUUUGUUCAGGGUUGUCCCCCCGCCCCCCGUCACUGCAUAAUUUCUCCUCUUACAAGCUGCUUUUGGCUUUCAUUAAUAACAGCUUCCUUUUAGAAGGUCUGAUAAGGAUAUUUAAGGAAGAAGAGAAUGACUCUGUUAUUAAAGGUGGCAUGGAGACUGUGGAGGGAAUAUUUUUUAAAGCACUACUCAUAUCCUUUAAACUAAAUUUUGCCAAAGCCCGAGACAACAUUAAGGAGAAAUUGUACCUUAAGUUAGUAAUUCCAAAUCUAUCUGAGUUGUAUACCCAUCAAAGACAAUACAGUUAUUAACAUAGAUGAAGGUAUGCUAUAGGCAUCAUUCAUUAUCUCUAUAUUGAAUAGGUGAAAGAUAACUGUAGUCAGGUGAAAGGCAUUCAUUAUUUUUAAGCUGAAAAGGGGAUCCUUGAAAACACUGAAAACCUCUACAACAAUCUUCAGGAAGCCUGCUAUCUUGGGAUUCACUAAUAAUAGGCCAAGAACAAAGGCAAGCAUCCAUUCCUCACUCCACCACUUUUCUAUUUCAGUGGGUGUCGUUGCUACGAUGAAGACUUUGGAAAUUUCCUUUCUCUUUUAGGACAGGGUCAGGAUUUAGGACUCAUAGCCUGAAAGCUCAUUACAUACUCCUUGUAACCAUCAGUCCAAGGUUCAGUUCACUAAAGUGCAUGUUCUAAAACAAGAGCUAUCCUCAUUCCAAAUUUUAAAAUAUGUACUCUGGCCGGUUGCAGUGGCUCACGCCUGUAAUCCCAGCACUUUGGCAGGCCGAGAUGGGCGGAUCUUUUGAGGUCAGGAGUUUGAGACCAGCCUGGCCAACAUGGUGAAACCCCGUCUCUACUAAAAAUACAAAAAUUAGCCAGGCAUGGUGGCAUUUGCCUGUAAUCCCAGCUACUCGGGAGGCUGAGGCAGGAGAAUCACUUGAACCUGGGAGGCAGAGGUUGCAGUGAGCUGAGAUUACACCACUGCACUCCAGCCUGGGUGACAGAGUGAGACUCCAUCUCAAAAACUGAAAAUAAAAAUAAAAAUAUGUAUUCUCCUAACUGAAAUAUUUACUUAAUCUGGAAAACAAUGUAACUAUUUUUAAAGUGGUUACAUCUAUUCUUGCUGAAGAACAAUAAACAGAAUUUUUUGACUAAGCAUAACCAAAUUUCAGAACAGUCUAAUCAAUGCCAAGUAUCCAAGGCAAACUCUAAUACCCAUCCAUUGUGCAAAACCACAAGCACGCAAGUAUUAAAUAAGAGCAAGCUGUCCUGAGCCCAUACCUAAUGAAUUUGUGUCUUAAAUAUUGUACAUUGUGUUUGAGGCUUGUCAAAACUGGGAUUAUGGCAAGAAAGGUUGCCUAACUCAUACCUUUCUGCCUCAAAUUCCAGGUGCUAAAGGCUAAUGGCAUUUUAAACAUCUUACAUUUUUAAAAAUUUAUAUUGCCUCUGCCAAACAGGCCUAAUAGUUAAAAGCAAGUUGAGACAAACCAGGCAGAUUCAGUGUGUGGAACAGGAAGGAUGUGCUUUAAAAAAAGGUGGAAUCCCUCAAAAAAUUCUAUAGGGAGACAGCAGCCUUAAUCUACAUAAUUCUUCAUCUCGCCAAUUCAGCCGCAGCCUUUAAAGAGUUAGUGUUAAUGGCUUUCUGGUUUGAAAACAAAAAUGCAUCUAUGUGGUUGAAAGUUUGGGAGGAGAUUCACCAAUAUCUGAGGAGAAGAUGGAGUGAAGGGAAUUCUUACUUUUUGCUUUAUACCUUUCUAUAAUAUUUAGAUUUUUUUUUACUGUAAGUAUGGAUCAAAUUGCAAAAUAAAGAAAAAUGCCAACCUUAGAAAAGACAAUAAAUGCACAAAAGAUAUAAACAGGAACAGCAAAUAUUUAUAUUUUUUCCAUUUUGCUCUUUUUAAAUCUAUGUUUAGAACUUUAUAUCUUGGGACUUAUGUAUAUAUAUACCUUUUAAAUAAAAUAAAUUUUCUAAAUAAAAA